CUUUCCAACCUCGAAUUCUGCUCAGCUCGCUUUGGCAGCUUGGUGGGCGGUGGGCGCGGGUGGCGGAGGCGAUUGAAGCUGCUGGCCCAGCAUGUGGUGCGCGAGCCCAGUUGCUGUGGUGGCCUUUUGCGCCGGGCUUUUGGUCUCUCACCCGGUGCUGACGCAGGGCCAGGAGGCCGGGGGGCGGCCAGGGGCCGACUGUGAAGUAUGUAAAGAAUUCUUGAACCGAUUCUACAAGUCACUGAUAGACAGAGGAGUUAACUUUUCGCUGGACACUAUAGAGAAAGAAUUGAUCAGUUUUUGCUUGGACACCAAAGGAAAAGAAAACCGCCUGUGCUAUUAUCUAGGAGCCACAAAAGACGCAGCCACAAAGAUCCUAAGUGAAGUCACUCGCCCAAUGAGUGUGCAUAUGCCUGCAAUGAAGAUUUGUGAGAAGCUGAAGAAGUUGGAUAGCCAGAUCUGUGAGCUGAAAUAUGGUAUAACACAGCCCCGUGUUUUUCCCAAAAAAACACUGGACUUGGCAUCAGUUGACCUGCGGAAGAUGAGAGUGGCAGAGCUGAAGCAGAUCCUGCAUAGCUGGGGGGAGGAGUGCAGGGCCUGUGCAGAAAAAACUGACUAUGUGAAUCUCAUUCAAGAGCUGGCCCCCAAGUAUGCAGCGACACACCCCAAAACAGAGCUCUGAUCUCCAAUGCCAGCACAUUUGUGACUUGUAAUUAGAGAGAAAAGUGACUCUCUAGGAUAUGGACAUGUUGAUUAAGGAUAACUGGGAAUGCAUCAUAUUUGGUCUCAUGCUUUUUGUGUUGGUAUUAUUCCUCAGAAUUUUGUUACGUGGGUUUAUGAGUGAAACUAAUACUACUGAUAACUUACAUUUGCAGUGUACCAAAAGCUAAAAGUUCCUUUCUCAUAAGUUUCUUGGAAUGACUAUGCCAGUUUUCAUUGCCUGUCUCCUAAAAGUGACCUACUGACAAAUUGAUGGAGUAAAUUGAUUCCAAGAAAGAAGAAGGCAUUCAGAGACUCCUCUCUGGAUGCAAUUUUAAAAUAUAUUGGACUAAAACAAAAGACACAACAGUCAGCUUAUCUAAUGCACAACUUCAAUCCCAAAUACAGAAUCAAAAGUUUUUUUCAAGUGAAUUUUCUGUUUUCACUCUAUAUUGUAGCUCUCUUUGGUAUCAGAAAUGGUCAGGCAGGAGUACUCGUUUUUCCCAUUGGAAGAAAACCCACUUAAACCUACUUAAAGAAAAUAGAGAGAUCAAGAAACCGUAUAAGUAUAGCCAAUGUUUGGCAAUUAUAUCAACAUUUACAUUGUUAAUUGAACCAAGCUCAAGGUCUUUUUCAUUCCUUACAGUCACAUAUCAGACAAGUUUUUGAUGGAAGAUUAAAGCAUAUUAAAAACACUCAUAGGCAACUUGGAACUUUA